CUGGCCCCGGCUUCUUGGCUGUCAAACAGAUGCAGCAACGUCGGCUCCUGCCGAGGAGCCCAAGGGGUCCCGGGAUCCGCCGCACAGGCUGGCACUGCUUGAAGAGGAGGCUACUCGGAGACUGCGCCGCGCGGGUAGAUCCGAAACGGGGCUGGGGCGGAGUGGGAAAAGGCCGGGUAUGCCUUGCAUGAUCGCGGGGAGCUCCUUCCUGUUUUUAUCCCACCUAGAGAAGCCGGGAAGUAGGGGUUUAGGUCCAAUUUGUUGGAGUACUUAAGGACUCGUUUGCACUUUCUUUUGGGGGAUGACAGUGGAUUCAUUGCCCUCGGAGGUUCAACCAGUUAUGAGUGAGGGAUUGGCCAGAAGAUCGGGGCGCAGGCAAGCAGGAGUGCUCUAUUAGGAUAAGCAAGUUUGACAGGAAGAAGCUACUCUUCUCCGAAUUACACAGAGGUGAUGUGUUCGUAUUGCACGUAGACGUGUGUAUAACAGGACCUCCUUCCCCGCGCCCCGCCACCCCGACACACACAGGAGCUGCCUAAAGUAUCCUUGCCUUGCAGAUUGGAGGCUCCCCAAAUAUUUUGCGAUCUGAGGAUCCAGCUCAAGUGAGGUGCCAUAGGACGUGUUCCUGAGUUUGCAUUGCACGGAGACCUUCCUGGAAUUUUUCAUUUGCAAGUCGGCUUAACCAAUUUUGCAUUGAGUCCUAGGCUGCUUGCACUCUGAAUUUGGGCUAUUCAGGUAGUGUGCUCAAAGUUGAAACCGCAUACAGCACAACUCAAGUUUGCAUCAGACUGGGAAGCGAACUUAAGCCAGCGGUGCGUGGCCCAGGAGUGGGAAAGGAAAUGGAUGCCUGAAGUGGAAGAGGUGGUGCAGAGGGGGCACCGCCCAUGCUGCCCUGCUUCCAACUGCUGCGCAUAGGGGGCGGCAGGGGCGGUGAUCUCUACACCUUCCACCCCCCCGCCGGGGCUGGCUGCACCUAUCGCUUGGGCCACAGGGCCGACCUGUGUGAUGUGGCCCUGCGGCCCCAGCAGGAGCCUGGCCUCAUCUCUGGGAUCCACGCCGAACUGCAUGCCGAGCCCCGGGGUGAUGACUGGAGGGUCAGCCUGGAAGACCACAGCAGCCAAGGUACUUUGGUCAAUAAUGUCCGACUCCCAAGAGGUCACAGGCUGGAAUUGAGUGAUGGAGACCUCCUGACCUUUGGCCCUGAAGGGCCCCCAGGAACCAGCCCCUCGGAGUUCUACUUCAUGUUCCAACAAGUACGAGUCAAGCCUCAGGACUUUGCUGCCAUUACCAUCCCACGGUCUAGGGGAGAAGCCCGGGUUGGGGCUGGUUUCCGGCCUAUGCUGCCCUCCCAGGGGGCUCCACAGCGGCCUCUCAGCACCUUCUCCCCUGCCCCCAAGGCCACACUGAUCCUAAACUCCAUAGGCAGCCUCAGCAAGCUCCGGCCCCAGCCCCUCACCUUCUCCCCUAGUUGGGGUGGACCAAAGAGCCUGCCUGUUCCCGCCCCACCUGGGGAAAUGGGGACCACGCCUUCUGCUCCACCACAACGCAAUCGGAGGAAAUCUGUUCACCGAGUGUUGGCGGAACUGGAUGAUGAGAGUGAGCCUCCUGAGAACCCGCCACCGGUCCUUAUGGAGCCCAGGAAGAAACUCCGUGUAGACAAAGCCCCACUGACUCCCACUGGAAAUCGACGUGGCCGUCCUCGGAAGUACCCAGUGAGCGCUCCCAUGGCUCCCCCUGCAGUUGGGGGCGGGGAGCCCUGUGCAGCUCCUUGUUGCUGCCUGCCCCAGGAAGAGACAGUGGCCUGGGUUCAGUGUGAUGGCUGUGACGUCUGGUUCCAUGUGGCCUGUGUUGGCUGCAGCAUCCAGGCUGCCAGGGAGGCCGACUUCCGAUGCCCAGGGUGCCGGGCUGGCAUUCAGACCUAAGGUCCACUGCCAAGGCACCAUCGGACACACCUGCCCAUGAGUAGACACAGCAGCGAGCAAAUAGGUCUGAUAAAUACCCCCCUUCCCUUCCCUCCCCAGGAGGGAAUGACUACAGGGAAGAAGGAUGGAUUGAUGUGGACUCAUUCAGGGCCUGGAGCAGACCCUGGUGGCCAAGACAGAAGAGAUGGUUUCCUGCCAAAGAUAUUGCCACCUCCAGGAAAUUGCCAGUGAGCUGGAAGUUCCCACUAUUACAAGCCAUAAGGCCAUGUUGCCAUGGACACCAGAAUAUCUGUAGUCAGAGCACCUAUCAGUUGCAAAAGCCAUGCCUGCAACCGAUGGAAAAUGUAAGAGGGAGUUCUUAAGGUUCUUGGUGGCAUCACCCAAGGCAUUCUGGGAAAACCUAGGGCCUGGCCCCAAAACUUCCCUACUCUGUGGCUAGUCCUGCUGCCAACAAAAUCGUAGCGACCUGGCUUUUCACAGCUUUGCUUUUAUUUCCAAGUCAAGGACAAGCCGCUUCAUUCACUCCUGGGCAUUUACUCUUCUUGUGGGUCUGUGAUAUUCCUUGCUUUCCAGGGAGAAUGUGCUUGGCAAGGUCUGGAGAACUAAUUCAGAAUCUUAGGGGAAGGGGAGAGAUGGAAAUACAAACCUGCUUACUGGAAAGGUGCAAAUAUAUGGGUUGAGCUGGAGGUAGGAAUACAGGUAAUUAAGGUUUCUAGUUUAAGGGAAAACAGAUCUAUUGCCAUUUAAAUAAGGUAACUGGGAUUUGGUUAAGUUCACAAAGAUAGCAGAAGAUUUAUUUACAGGCUUCACCUGUACUGUCAGGGCAAGAGAAAGCCUGGUAAACCAGCUACAGCAGUUUACCAGUGUGAUGGCUGUGACACAGCUCCACUCCACGGGUGGACACAGCAGAGGGCAACUGGGCUGGCCUGGUUCAGUGUGAAUCAAACCGCUUAACCCACACAUGGUACAUGUGAUUUUCUUUUGUGAGCCUUACACCAAGCCAAACUAUUGUCAAAGCAUCAUUUCUAUAGAAAUAAAGCCUUAUCUUGACCUGUUCUAUUAAAACCUGCCACACCCGCCCUUUCCUACCUAGAUUUAAUGAGCCCAAGUUUUUAAAAUGGAAGAAAUGACUCUGGGGCAAAGACCCCUAAUGAACUAGUGGCAGAGCCAGGAAUAAAACUUGAGUAACUAAUGAGUCACUUAUGGGCAGAGUAUGCAAAAACCUUAAGUGGAAACCAAAUAGACCCUGGUAUCAAGAAAGCACAAAGUAUUAAUAGAAGUUUCUGGUUGGGGUGAUCUAGGUUCAACAGAAAUAAGAUGAUUUCUAAGUAUAAAGCCAUUUAAGAAUUCCAGAGUAGGGUGGGAAAGCAAAAAGCCAGCUCUGAACAGGUAACAGCUACAUGGUGACUGAGUCUAUGGGCAAAAGUUCUUGCAUCACAGGCUUUUGGGAACUAGCCUAUCACAGGGCCCUGUACAAAUAAACUUGGCUGCAAUCCCA